GUCGCAGGUCCACGCCGUAAACAGACAACAUGGCGGCCGCGGUGGCGGCGGCACCUGGGGCCUUGGGAUCCCUGCAUGCUGGCGGCGCCCGCCUGGUGGCCGCUUGCAGUGCGUGGCUCUGCCCGGGGUUGAGGCUGCCCGGCUCGUUGGCAGGCCGGCGAGCGGGCCCGGCGAUCUGGGCCCAGGGCUGGGUACCUGCGGCCGGGGGUCCCGCCCCGAAAAGGGGCUACAGCUCUGAGAUGAAGACGGAGGACGAGCUGCGGGUGCGGCACCUGGAGGAGGAGAACCGAGACUCUAGUUCCAUGGCUGCUGAUCACUAUAGAAUUGUGGUGCUUGGAAUAAACAGAGCUUAUGGCAAAAAUUCACUCAGUAAAAAUCUUAUAAAAAUGCUAUCAAAAGCUGUGGAUGCUUUGAAAUCUGAUAAGAAAGUACGGACCAUAAUAAUCAGGAGUGAAGUCCCAGGGAUAUUCUGUGCUGGUGCUGACCUUAAGGAAAGAGCCAAAAUGAGUUCCAGUGAAGUUGGUCCUUUUGUCUCCAAAAUAAGAGCAGUGAUUAACGAUAUUGCUAAUCUUCCAGUACCAACAAUUGCAGCAAUAGAUGGACUCGCUUUAGGUGGUGGUCUUGAACUGGCUUUAGCCUGUGAUAUACGAGUAGCAGCUUCCUCUGCAAAAAUGGGCCUGGUUGAAACAAAAUUGGCGAUUAUUCCUGGUGGAGUGACUUCCUCCACUGAAGUCUUGAAUCCCUCCAAGUCAUCCAUGAAGAUUGGAAUCAUCAUCUUCCAAACUCCUGUUAAUAUUGAUAUUCUGGCCUCUUCCCAUGAAUCAUGAAUGUUCUUAAAGGGAUCUAGAAUGGCAGAUCCUUUCCAGAAGGUUUUCAAUUUAAUUUGCCCAGAUCCAUAAGAGGAAUCACUGUCUAUGGCAGCUAUAGCCUUAUGAAAUGUGGUUUUUGUUUUGUUUUGUUUUUUUGAGACGGAGUCUCGCUCUGUUGCCAGGUUGGAGUGCAGUGGUGUGAUCUCGGCUCACUGCAACCCCUGCCUCCCCGGUUCAAGGGAUUCUCCUGCCUCAGCCUCCUGAGUAGCUGGGACUACAGGUGCACACCACCGUGCCCAGCUAAUUUUUGUAUUUUUUGUAGAGACGGAGUUUCACCAUGUUGGCCAGGAUGGUCUUGAUCUCUUGACCUCAUGAUCUGCCUGCCUCAAGCUCCCAAAGUGCUGGGAUUACAGGCGUGAGCCACCACGCCCAGCCUGAAAUGUGUGUCUUAAAUAAUAAGACUUGAAAGUAGACUGAUCCAUGGGCUGUGGAAUGGCUGUUAUGUUAUCAGGCAUGAAAACAACAUUCAUCUCCUUGUCUGUCUCUGUCAGAGCUCUUGGGUAACCAGGACAUUGUCACUGAACAGUAAUAUUUUGAAAGAACUCUUUUUUUUGAGCAGUAGGUCUCAGCAGUGGGCUUUAGUAUUCAGUAAACUAUGCUGGAAACCAGAUGCACUGUCAUCCAGGUUUUAUUUGUUCCAUUUAUAAAGCAUAAGCAGAGUUAACUUAGCAUAGUUCUUAAGGGCUCUAGAAGUUUGGGAAUGAUAAGUGAGCAGUGGCUUUAACUAAAAGCCACCAGCUGCAUUAGUCCCUAACAAGGGAGUCAGUCUGUCCUUUGAAGCUUUGAAGCCAGGCAUUGACUUCUCUUCUGUAGCUAUGAAAGUCCUGGAUAACAUCUUCUUCUAAUAGUAGGCUGUUUUGUCUACACUGAAGAUGUGUUAUUCAGUGUAGGCACCUUCAUCAGUGAUCUUAGCUAGAUCUUCUGGAUAAUUUGCUGCAGCUUCUACAUCAGCACGUGCUGCUUCACCUUGUACUUCUGUGUUACGGUAGAUGGCUUCUUUCCUUAACCAUGAAGUAGCCUCUGCUAGCUUCCAACUUUUCUUCUGCAGCUUCUUCACUUGUCUCAGACUUAACUCUAGAAUUAAAGAGAGUUAAGAGUUAUAGUUAAAGAGAGUUAGGGCUUUGCUCUGGAUUAGGCUUUGGCUUAGGGGAAUGUUGUGGCUAGUUUGAUCUUCUUUACGGACCACUAAAACUUUCUGCAUAUCAGCAAUAAGGCUAUUCUGCUUUCUUCUUAUUCCUGUGUUCACUGGAGUAGCACUUCUAAUUACCUUCAAGAAACGUUGCUUUGCAUUGGCAACUAAGCCUAAGUGGUGCAAGAGGCCUAGCUUUUGGCUGAUCUCAGCUUUUGACAUGCCUUCCUCACUAAGCUUAAUCAUUUCUAGUUUUUGAUUUCCAGUGAGAGACGUGUGGAUCUUUGCUCUACUUGAACACUGCAGAAGUCACUGGAAGGUUAUUCAUUGGCCUAAUUUCAAUACUGUUUUGUCUCAGGGAAUAGAGAGACCCAAGGAAAGGGAGAGAGAUGGGGGAACAGCCCGUUGGUUGAGCCGUCAGAAUACAUGCAUUUAUUGGUUAAGUUUGCCAUCCUAUGUGGGCGUGGUUCAUGGUGCCCCAAAAUAAUUACAGUAGUAACAACAAAGAUUAAUGAUCACAGGUUACCAUAAGAGAUACAAUAAUGAAAAGGUUUGAAAUAUUGUGAAAAUUACCAAAAUAUGGCACAGAGACAUGAAGUAAGCACAUACUGUUGGAAAAAUGGUGCCAAUAGACUUGCUUGAUGCAGGGUUACCAUUAAUUUGUAAAAAUGUAGUAUCUGUGAAGUACAAUAAAGGGAAGCACGACAAAAUGAGGUAUGCCUGUAUGCCCUAUUUUUAGCUUACGUAGACAGUGAAGAUGGUAGUUCUUAAGUUUUAAGUUACUGUGCUAAUUACAUUUUUGUCACUGUUUGGAUCUAUUUUCCUAAAGGAUUACACAAAUAUUUUAAAGCUUUUAUGCGUGCAUUUAAAUGUGUGUGUCCUCACCAACAGCUUCAUGCAGACAGUGAAACCCCAAGUGGAAGAAGAAGAGAGGUGCCUGGGUGCGGUGUCUUAUGCCUGUAAUCCUAGCACUUUGGGAGGCCGAGGCGGGUGGAUCACUUGAGGUCAGGAGUUUGAGACCAGCCUGGCCAACCUGGUGAAACCCCGUCUCUACUAAAAAUAGAAGAAUUAGCCAGUCAUGGUGGUGCGUGCUUGUAAUCACAGCUACCUGGGAGGCUGAGGCAGGAGAAUUGCUUGAACCCAGAUGGUGGAAAUUGCAGUGAGCCGAGAUCACACCACCGCACUCCAGCAGCCUGGGUGACAGAGCGAGACUCCGUCUCAAAAAAAAAAAAAAAAAAAAGAGGGUUCCCAGGCUUUGUACCACCUUUCUUGUGUUUCUCUGCAGUGGGACAAAAGUUGCGGUUAGUGGGUAGCCUGAACUUAGAGCUGAAGAGGUGUUGUUUCUUCUAUUCCUAUGAAAAAAAUAGAUGAGCUUCUGUUCUUGAAAGAGCCGUUUAAGAAAACAUCUUUCCAAAAUUGAUAAUGAAAUCUUGCAUCACCCAAUAAAUCUGAAAUUUUUGGUCUUUUGAUUCAGAGAAUUUGGAGGCAUUCCCAUUUUGUGAAGUCAUUCUUUCAAAAAGUAGACUUCAUUUAAGGAUAUGCAUGUUAUAGUAACCUUCCUUGGAACUUUUUUUUUUUUUUUUUUUUUUUUGACACGGAGUCUCACUCUGUCGCCAGACUGGAGUGCAAUGGCACAAUCUUGGCUCAUGGUACCUUUUAUGUAUGCUAAAUGAUGCUUAGAGUAUGAAUGAAACAACAGUAACAAUGUAAAUAUUAAACUCAGUGUUGAACAUGGAAGACAUACUUGCAUAUGAAUUGGUUAAAAUUGUGUGGUUAACCUUAUCAUUAAAAGAGUAUUUAUUCUGAUAGGUAGAAAUUUAAAACAUAGGUUACAGUGAAAUUGAAGACUGCCCAGAUGAAUGUGUAAGACUCCCCAUGUUUUCUACUUUGGUAAUUGAUGAAAAUGUUAUUCUUGUAGGCCAAAACAUUUAAUAUAUACUUACUCUAUUAUGCCUGCCUUUUUCACUGUGACUAAUAAAAAACACCAGAAGGAUUUAUAAGACAGUGGAUCAAUUUAAAAAGAAUUCCCAGAUAACUAAUAUGUGAAAUAAAGCAAAAUUUAGCAAAAGGGUGAUGUGACAUAUUUCUGAAAUUCUUUUGAGAAGUAAGCAUUUGUUGGUAAUGAGGAUGUGAUUAAUCCUAGAAGAUAGAAAGAUAGUGGCUGUAGUGGGUUGGAUGGCAUGCCGCCUCCACCCCCACCCCCCCAACAGACACCAAGAGAUGUCAGCCUGGAAGGAAAAGCAUCUUGCACGUGUAAUUAAGGAUCUCAAGAUGAGAUCAUCCUGAAUUAUCUGAGAGAGGCUUAAAUCCAAAGACAAGGGGUCCUUAUAAGAAAGAGGAAGGCACAGAAGAAGAGAAGGUGAUGCGAAGACAGAAACAGAGUGCAGUAAUACAUCUACAUGCCAAGGAAUGCCAAGGGUUGUCGGCAGCCACGGGAAGCCAUGGGUGAGAGGCAUGGAACAGAUUUUCUCACAGAGCCUCUCGAAGGAACCACACUACAAACACCUUGAUUUUGGAUUUCUGGCCUCCAAAACUGAGAGAGAAUAAAUUUCAGUUGUUCAGAGGUACCAGGUUUAUGGCAAUUUGUUAUAGCAAUGAAUACAGCGACUUUUUGGUGAUGUUUACAUGAUUUUUGGGGACAGAUGGGGGUUAGUAGGUGGCAGAAAUUUGGGGAGGGAGCAAGAUGAACUUGGUAAUUUGGAUAUUUACUGUGACUUGAUUAUGAAAAGUUUUGUGUUACAACUACCAGAAGAUAGAGAGCAGUGUUUGGUUUGAUUAGAUGAGAAAAGAUAGAUUAUGCUAUAACAACCUCUUCUGUCUUGUCUUGUGAACUCACUGUGCCAUACCAUAUGAGGUCUAGAAACUAGAAUUUUUUCCCAAUAUACUUAAGUUCUUUAGAGUCCUCUGCAAUAGUGGCUGCAUUAAUUAGAACCUACUUUUUGUAGGUUUGAUUGAAUUUGGACUACAUAUUCUGACAAAUAGAAUUAUUUUUCUAGUUUCUAUUAAAUAAAUUUGUCAUAAAAGUCAGAAUGCUUUGACAUAUUCCCAUGUACUUACAAAGGAUGGUUGUCUUUUUCUUUUCUUUCUUUUUUUUGUUUGGAGACAGGGUCUUGCUUGGUCACCCAGGCUAAAGGACAGCGAUGUAAUGAUAGCUCACUGCAGCCUCAAACUCUUGGGUUCGAGAUCUUCCCACCUCGGCCUCUGGAGUAGCUGGGACUAUAGGCACACAGCACUGCACUCGGCUAAUUUUCUUCUCUUUUUGUAGAGGCAGGGUCUCACUAUGUUGCCCAAGCUGGUCUUGAACUUCUGGCCUCAAGCAAUCCUCCUGCCUUGGCUUCCCAAAGUGCUGGGAUUACAGGCAUGAGCCACUGCCUCUGACCUCUUUUGUCCUAAGUGAGUUUGAGGAAUGUAUUUUAGUUCCUCUUUUAAUACCAUGAAGCUUUCAAGUUCAUAGCUCAUAAAAUGUUAUGUAGCUUUGAAUUUUUUAAUGUAAAUGAAAAUCAGAUUCAUUUUCGUUAUUAAUAAAAAUUUCAAUAGUAUUCACAUUUAGAUAAGAGAUGCACAGAAUUUUUGGUCUACUUUUAAAUUAAUAUUACAGUUCUUAAAGUACCCUAGGUGAUGCCUGUUCUUUUGAAACAGCAGAGAUUUUAUUUUAAAAAUACGUUUUUGUGUUUAUUACCUAAAGGAGCUAUUCUGAAAUUUUUAUGUAGAAAAAUCUUCUUCUGCUCCAUCCACAGAAGAUUUUUUAUCCAUAGAUAUUUUUGCCAUCUCCUUUCUCCUCUUUCCUUUGUUGUAGAUGAUAUGAAAAGACUGCUUUUUUCAAAAAUUGUGUUUUUAAAUUGGUGAAUUUUGCCAUGCCUAAAGUGAUCUCUGAGAUAUCCUCCUUUUGGGUAUAAACAUUUCUGUUAAAUGUUGUAAAGAGCUUUCUAUAAUAGACACAGUAGACUGUAUUUAAUUUUUUUCUCCCUUCUUGGUAGAUCUCUUUUGGUUAAAAGAAAAUGCGUCACUUGCCUCCUAUUAUAGAAGCUUGUAUGAGCAGCCAGGGGUGCACUCUGCAGGGAAGGCUUGGCCAUUGCCAGUGAGCCUUGCUCCACUGUAGCUGCCUUAGCUCUUCCUCUUUUCCAGAUGAGCAGGUGCUGACAGCCAAAAAAAUAGAAAAUAAGUGGGGAGAAUUCAAAUAUGGGGAAAAUAUUGUGGAAAAAAUAGAUGCUUAAUUUUUCUUCUUAAUAUUAUGUAGAAAGUAAAUAUCUUUGGGUAAAAUACAUGAAUUGUAGCCACUCUAGAAAACAGAUGUUUAAAAUCUGGCAAAUAAUCUUCUGCUAAGUUAUUACAGGUCCAUGAUUUCAUACUGGCCAGCAUUUGUAAGUUAAUCCAAAUGAAAUUGUAUCUCCUUAUUUGAAUUUACUGUACAUUUGAUAAAGACAAGAGAAUUAAUGUGAUGCUAUUGAUUGUCAUAUCAUCACUUCUGGCCUUUUCUGAUAGCAGUUCACAGCAAAACAAUUUGUCAAAAAAUAGUGUUUUGUUUUGUUUUGUUUUCUUUACCUGAGCUUUGACCUGCGUAGCAAUAUGUUGAUUUUUAAGGUAUGUUUUGUAAAUUAAAAAAAUGCUAUUAUAAAAUAAUGACUUUGAAGAGAUGGUAAUAUUUCUAUUGAACAUAUUAAUGGACCACUGCUAUCAUGUAGUUUUUAAUUUAGAAGGCUCAAUUUUAGUUUUUAUUAGAAAGAAUAUUGUUUAGUAUCAAAUGACUAUUAAAAGUAUAUAGUGCAAUAAAAAGAAAGACGUGAAGGAAUGUGGAAACAUUAAAACAAAAUCGAACCUCCUUAAGUAGUAGUUAUAUCAGAUGUAAUUAAAAGAUGGGAUGUAAUUUGACUAUCAAAUACUUGAACCAAUGCUUUUAUUUGUAAUAUAUAUAUGUGUAUAUAUGUUUUUGAUUACCAAUAUUAAACACAAAGUGAAACACUAUUGAUUUGAAGCACUGGCCCAUUUAAAAAUAAUUUAAAUGGUUACCCCAGAACCUUGUCGUAAUUUUAUUGGGGAUUUUUGUACAAUAUAUAGCCCUAGUUUCGUCUCCAACGUUCUCACCUUUAAGAAAGCAUUUACAUUUCCUAUCCUCUCCCAACUGGGAGAAUAUGCAAAUAUUAUAAAAUAAAAUUCUCUUUUAGAAAUAGUUCCUAAAACAGUACUUUCCUUUAAUACAUUUGCAAGGAUGAAAUACAAGUUCAGAGGAUUAAGAUCCUUUUAUUUGACAGUAUCUCUUUAAAUUUACAGAGAAAAUAGUGGCAGAUUUUCUAAUUCCCGCUCUUUGUUCUUACCUCUUCUACUGGAGGUUUUGGGGUCUGUGUCAGGAAACCUUAUUAUUACUAAGGUAAUUUGUUAAGGCUUUUUGCUUGGGUGUACACCACUGGGAUUGAGAUGCUUUGUAUUUCCACUGCUCUGUGAAUUCCUUUUUUAUUCCCCCCAGCUUCUGGGGGGAGGCAUAUUCAAACUAGGAAGUUUGAAUAGCAGUAAAACACACAUUUUUAUACCCUUUACAAAGAUCUAUUCCUUCCAUUUUCUUUCUCCUUCCAUUCCCCAAAUCCUUCUUUCUCAUAGAAACAUUUCAAAAUAUAGAUGAGUCUUUCAAUAUUUCAGCAUACGUUUUCUAAGAAUCAAGAAUGGUCUCUUACAUAAUCAACACUAUUAUCACACCCAAGAAUAUUAACAGGAAUUUAGUAAUAUUAUUUAAUAUAUGAUUCAUAAUUGGAUUUCUCCAGUUGUCUGUAGCCGUCUUUUUGUAUUUUGUUUUUCCAGUUCAGGAUUAAUUUUUCAUUUGGUUAAAUCUGUAGUUUUUUCAAAUUUGAAAGAGUACCUCAUUCAUGUUUUUUGUUUUCUAUAACACUAAUUUAACUUUUCAUGUUGCAGUAAUUUCAGAUUUACAGAAUAGUUACAAAGAUAGUAUAAAUCACUCUUAUGUACGCUUUACCCAGCUUCCUCAAAUAUUAACAUGUUAUAGAACUGUACCACAGUUAACAAAAGUAGACAGUUAAUACUGGUAUGUUAUUACUAACUAAUCUGUAGACCUUACUCAAAUGCUGUCACUUUUCUCACAAGUGUCCUUUUUCUGGUUCAAGACAGUUGAGGCCUCCACGUUGCAUUUAGUUGGUGUGUCUCCUUUGUCUCUUGUAUUUAAUCAGUGUAUAAAUUUGUAUUUAAUCAUCUUGACAAUUUAGAAGAGUGCCAGUCUGUAAUUAUGUGGAAUGUCUUUUAUUUUUGAGUUUGCCUAAUGUUUCCUCAUGAAUAAAUUAAGAUUAUUCAUUUUUGGCAA